AGAGGCGCUGCGGCUGUGAUCCAGGCUGGGGCGAGACCAUGUCGGACCUGGGCUCGGAGGAGUUGGAGGAGGAGGGAGAGAAUGAUAUUGGGGAAUAUGAGGGGGGUCGGAAUGAGGCAGGCGAAAGGCACGGACGUGGGAGGGCACGGCUACCCAACGGGGACACCUACGAAGGGAGCUACGAAUUCGGUAAAAGACAUGGCCAGGGGAUCUACAAAUUUAAAAAUGGUGCUCGAUAUAUCGGAGAAUAUGUUAGAAAUAAAAAGCACGGUCAAGGCACUUUUAUAUAUCCAGAUGGAUCCAGAUAUGAAGGAGAGUGGGCAAAUGACCUGCGGCACGGCCAUGGCGUAUACUACUACAUCAAUAAUGACACCUACACUGGAGAGUGGUUUGCUCAUCAAAGGCAUGGGCAAGGCACCUAUUUAUACGCGGAGACGGGCAGUAAGUAUGUUGGCACCUGGGUGAACGGACAGCAGGAGGGCACGGCCGAGCUCAUUCACCUGAACCACAGGUACCAGGGCAAGUUCUUGAACAAAAAUCCUGUUGGCCCUGGAAAGUAUGUAUUUGAUGUUGGGUGUGAACAACAUGGUGAAUAUCGUUUAACAGAUAUGGAAAGAGGAGAAGAGGAAGAGGAGGAAGAAUUAGUAACUGUUGUUCCAAAAUGGAAAGCUACCCAAAUCACUGAAUUGGCCCUGUGGACACCAACUCUCCCCAAAAAGCCGACCUCUACGGAUGGACCUGGCCAAGACGCUCCAGGAGCUGAGAGUGCAGGAGAACCCGGGGAGGAGGCCCAGGCUCUGCUGGAGGGCUUCGAGGGUGAGAUGGACAUGAGGCCUGGAGAUGAAGAUGCAGACGUCCUCCGGGAAGAGAGCCGGGAGUAUGACCAGGAGGAGUUCCGCUAUGACAUGGAUGAGGGAAACAUUAAUUCUGAAGAAGAAGAAACUAGACAGUCAGACCUCCAGGACUAAGAUGAAGUGAGCCGAGAGGAGAUCGUAUCAUAAGAAUGCUUCUGUCGUUAGCCGGGUGCAGUGCUGUGUGUAUCUAGUUCCAGCUACUUGAGAGGCUGAGGCAGGAGGAUUGCUUGAGUCCAGAAAGUGGCAGUUGCAGUGAGUGGAGAUCGCGCCACUGCUCUCCAGCCUGGGUGGCAGAGCGAGACCCUGUCUCAAAAAAUAAACAAAAACAAAAUGCUUCUGUCAGUUAACAAUCUUUAUUAGAGGGUUUUUAGUCUUUCUUUCUCAGCUGUAUGUUAAGUUGAUUGACAAAUGCAAAUAAACGUCUUUAUUAUCCUUUCUUUCUGAAA